GAACUCCCGGCAAAGCCCAGCUACAGGCGGGCGACUGCGGGGGGCCCCUGAGGCGGCGGGGGCCAUGGCUGGGGUCGCGUGCUUGGGAAAAGCUGCCGACGCAGAUGAAUGGUGCGACAGCGGCCUGGGCUCCCUGGGUCCGGACGCAGCGGCCCCCGGAGGACCUGGGUUGGGCGCGGAGUUGGGCCCGGGGCUGUCGUGGGCUCCCCUCGUCUUCGGCUACGUCACUGAGGAUGGGGACACGGCACUGCACUUGGCUGUGAUUCAUCAGCAUGAACCCUUCCUGGAUUUUCUUCUAGGCUUCUCGGCCGGCACUGAGUACAUGGACCUGCAGAAUGACCUAGGCCAGACAGCCCUGCACCUGGCAGCCAUCCUGGGGGAGACAUCCACGGUGGAGAAGCUGUACGCAGCAGGCGCCGGGCUGUGUGUGGCGGAGCGUAGGGGCCACACGGCGCUGCACCUGGCCUGCCGUGUGGGGGCACACGCCUGUGCCCGUGCCCUGCUUCAGCCCCGCCCCCGGCGCCCCAGGGAAGCCCCCGACACCUACCUCGCUCAGGGCCCUGACCGUACUCCCGACACCAACCAUACCCCUGUCGCCUUGUACCCCGAUUCCGACUUGGAGAAGGAAGAAGAGGAGAGUGAGGAGGACUGGAAGCUGCAGCUGGAGGCUGAAAACUACGAGGGCCACACCCCACUCCACGUGGCCGUUAUCCACAAAGAUGUGGAGAUGGUCCGGCUGCUCCGAGAUGCUGGAGCUGACCUUGACAAACCGGAGCCCACGUGCGGCCGGAGCCCCCUUCAUUUGGCAGUGGAGGCCCAGGCAGCCGAUGUGCUGGAGCUUCUCCUGAGGGCAGGCGCGAACCCUGCUGCCCGCAUGUACGGUGGCCGCACCCCACUCGGCAGUGCCAUGCUCCGGCCCAACCCCAUCCUCGCCCGCCUCCUCCGUGCACACGGAGCCCCUGAGCCCGAGGGCGAGGACGAGAAAUCCGGCCCCUGCAGCAGCAGUAGCGACAGCGACAGCGGAGACGAGGGCGUGAGUCAGGAGGAGAGACAGGGCAGCCCAGCUGGGGGGUCAGGAUAGACCGGCAGGCAAGAAGCCCAAGAAGAUAAUUAGGCACCGACCUUGGGCUGCUGUUAGAGAACUCAGGCAGCAGCGCCAGUGACACGGGGCACUAGUCAGGAGAGACCUGGACAGGGGUGGUGGGAAGAGCUUGGGCAGAAGUGGCUGAAAAACUAAGGCAGUGGCAAAGGUAGAACUCAGGCAGGGGUGGAGAAAAGGCGUUGGUCGCAGUGAUUGGUGAACACAGCGGGGGUGGGUGGUAGCGCUGGGGGUGAUUUUAGGCAGCAAGAAUUGGAGAACUCACACUGCGAAAAGAAAACCUUGGGUGGCAGUGAUUUGAACACCGGCAGUGCUGGGGCAGGACCCGAGCCAGCGGUGGGGAGAGAUAUAGUCAGAGAACCCAGCAAUACAGAUCCGUCCUUGGGCAAGGCGCGGUGCUGGAUGAUGGGUGCGGAGGAAUUUGGGUAAAGGCAGAGGGAAGGGGUGGAGGAGGGCCAGCUCAGUUGCCGAAACUCUGGAGUGGCGGCUGGCUAGAAAUUGGUCUGUAGAAAUGACCUUGAAAAUGGAGUUCUGGCCAGGUGCGGUGGCUCACGCCUGUAAUCCCAGCACUUUGGGAGGCCGAGGCAGGCAGAUCACGAGGUCAGGAGUUCGAGACCAGCCUGGCCAACAUGGCAAGACCCUGUCUCUACUAAAAAUACAAAAAUUAGCUGGGCGUGGUGGCGCAUGCCUAUAAUCCCAGCUACUUGGGAGGCUGAGGUAGGAGAAUUGCUUGAACCUGGGAGGUGGAGGUUGCAGUGAACCUAGAUCACGCCACUGCAUUCCAGCCUGGGCAACAGAGCGAGACUCCAUCUUAAAAAAAAAAAAAAAAAAAAGAAAGAAAAGAAAAUGGAGUUCUGAGAGCUAGGAAACUGGGAGGUUGAGCCAGGAGCAGGGGAACUUGGGCUUUGAGGCGAGACCUAAUUCUUAGGGUGCUCUAUGAGGACAUGGGUGGUGGGCAAAGUGACAGCCGCCUGAGCCCCUCUGCCUGGUCCCCUUUGCCCCCAGGAUGAAUACGACGACAUUGUGGUUCACAGCAGCCGCAGCCAAACCCGGCUGCCUCCCACCCCAGCCUCAAAACCUCUUCCUGACGACCCCCGCCCCGUGUGAUUUGUUUCAUUGUUAAUAUAAUUUCCAGUUUAAUAAACAAAACCCUAGUUCUGACAA